GAGUCUUACCUCGUUGUGGCGUCAGAACCGCCGUCGCUCGCUCCCUUCUCGGCAGUGGUACCUGUUCCCGGUGUCCCUGAGGACGUGCGGGCCAGGUACGGCCCCGAAAGUAGGAAGCGGAGGGGGAGCAGGUAAGGGACCCGGAGGGGGUCCCUGGGGUUGGUGUGGGGGAGCAGCCCCGGCCUGCGGAUGCCCCAUCCCCGGGCAGCAGCGCGGAGACGCAGCCGGUCCACGAUGCAGCCCCGGGGCCCCGCCGCGGGACCGCGAGCCUUGUGUGAGCGGAGGGGUGCCCGGCCCCGCGGGAGCCGGCGAUCCUGAGGCUACGACCUUUCGGAAGCACCUGCCUCCGUCACCAGCGCAAGCUUUUCCAACACCCCUGCUCCGCCCUUCUUGAUGCAGAAAAUGGUGGUUUGCGGGGCCAAGUGUUGCGGCGACGCACCUCACGUCGAGAAUCGGGAGGAGGAGACUGCAAGGAUAGGCCCAGGAGUAAUGGAGUCCAAAGAGGAACGAGCGUUAAACAAUCUCAUCGUGGAAAAUGUCAACCAGGAAAAUGAUGAAAAAGAUGAAAAGGAGCAAGUUGCUAAUAAAGGGGAGCCCUUGGCCCUACCUUUGAAUGUUAGUGAAUACUGUGUGCCUAGAGGAAACCGUAGGCGGUUCCGCGUUAGGCAGCCCAUCCUGCAGUAUAGAUGGGACAUAAUGCAUAGGCUUGGAGAGCCACAGGCAAGGAUGAGAGAGGAGAAUAUGGAAAGGAUUGGGGAGGAGGUGAGACAGCUGAUGGAAAAGCUGAGGGAAAAGCAGUUGAGUCAUAGUUUGCGGGCAGUCAGCACUGAUCCCCCUCACCAUGACCAUCACGAUGAGUUUUGCCUUAUGCCCUGAAUCCUGAUGGUUUCCCUGAAGUUAAUAGGGAGACCCCUGCUUCCUAAACUUACACAUUUGUGGUGUACCUUUGUCGUAAACGUUUUGAUGUUACCUAUUUCUUGUGGGUCUCCUAUUACCAGCUUCUAAAUGAAUGUUGUUUUUGACCCAGUUUGUAAGUUUCUGUCAGCAGGAGAGUUUUACCUAUUGCAUGGAAAGAUGCUCAUUAUAUAUUGUGAAGUUAAUAAAACAGUUUUAAAAAGCA